AGCAGGGUGCUUACUAAAUGGUGGUUUGGACUCACAUUCUUGCCUUCUACUUUAGUAUAAAAGGAAGAGGGGCAUUGUUGAUUAUCUGGCUGCUUCCUGCCGAAUAGGGGAGCUGUAAUCAGGGUUUGGGUUUUGAAGCAGUGGGUGUUGGACUUCAGAGUUGUUUUCCUGGAGGCACUGGUACUGGACUUGGCAGAGGAGAAGGAUGGUAUCAAUGUGUUGCUGGGUGGCCGCCUGGACAGGGGAGUUUAGCCUUCGGGAGAUAAAGCGGGAUAUGAAGAUGCAAGAGGUACCAAACAGAGUCUUAGCCCCCGAACAGAGUUUGAAGAACACAAAAACAUCAGAAUAUCCAAUAAUAUUUGUGUAUUACCUCAGGAAGGGUAAGAAAAUAAAUUCAAAUCAACUGGAGAAUGAACAGUCCCAAGAGAACUCCAUCAAUCCAAUCCAAAAGGAGGAGGACGAAGGCGUAGACUUAUCUGAAGGAUCUUCAAAUGAGGAUGAAGACCUAGGCCCAUGUGAAGGACCUUCAAAGGAGGACAAAGAUCUAGACUCAUCUGAAGGAUCCUCACAGGAGGAUGAAGACCUAGGCUUAUCUGAAGGAUCUUCACAGGACAGUGGGGAGGAUUAGUCACACAUGGAGAAACCAAAUUGGACAAAUCAUCACCACUGAUGGCGAUGAUUACAAUAAAAUCAAGUUUAAGGAGCUGA